ACUUGUAGGAAAGCCUCUUUGCAUUUAGACGUAAUUGAACUGGAAGGAAGGAGACUGGCCAGGGAAUAGGGGGAAAGAAAUUCUCCCGUUGCUCCUCCUACUGUUUAUCACUUGCCUCCGGACUGUCUUCCAAACCAAGCUCAGCUGCAUCAAGGUGGCAGCAGAAUACCCUGUGCAAGUGCCAGCGUCUUCUUAGCCGCUCUGUGCAUCCCAGGCUGCCCUGUUAUCUGGCCACCGUCCCUGGCCAUUGGGACUGCUUCUGAUGGCUCUGGCCUCUGCUGCCCCAGGGAGCAUCUUCUGUAAGCAGCUCCUUUUCUCUCUCCUGGUUUUAACAUUACUUUGCGAUGCUUGUCAGAAAGUUUAUCUUCGAGUUCCUUCUCAUCUUCAGGCUGAAACACUUGUAGGCAAAGUGAAUCUGGAGGAGUGUCUCAAGUCGGCCAGCCUAAUCCGGUCCAGUGACCCUGCCUUCAGAAUUCUAGAAGAUGGCUCAAUUUACACAACACAUGACCUCAUUUUGUCUUCUGAAAGGAAAAGUUUUUCCAUUUUCCUUUCAGAUGGUCAGAGACGGGAACAACAAGAGAUAAAAGUUGUACUGUCAGCAAGAGAAAACAAGUCUCCUAAGAAGAGACAUACCAAAGACACAGCCCUCAAGCGCAGCAAGAGACGAUGGGCUCCUAUUCCAGCUUCAUUGAUGGAGAACUCGUUGGGUCCAUUUCCACAACACGUUCAGCAGAUCCAAUCUGAUGCUGCACAGAAUUACACCAUCUUUUAUUCCAUAAGUGGGCCAGGCGUGGACAAAGAACCCUUCAAUUUGUUUUACAUAGAGAAAGACACUGGGGAUAUCUUUUGUACAAGGAGCAUUGACCGUGAGAAAUAUGAACAGUUUGCGUUAUAUGGCUAUGCAACAACUGCAGAUGGCUAUGCACCAGAAUAUCCACUCCCUUUGAUCAUCAAAAUUGAAGAUGAUAAUGAUAACGCCCCAUAUUUUGAACACAGAGUGACUAUCUUUACUGUGCCUGAAAAUUGCCGAUCCGGAACUUCAGUGGGAAAAGUGACCGCCACAGACCUUGACGAACCUGACACUCUCCAUACUCGUCUGAAAUAUAAAAUCUUACAACAAAUCCCAGAUCAUCCAAAGCAUUUCUCCAUACACCCAGAUACCGGUGUCAUCACCACAACUACACCUUUUCUGGAUAGAGAAAAAUGUGAUACUUACCAGUUAAUAAUGGAAGUGCGAGACAUGGGUGGUCAGCCUUUCGGUUUAUUUAAUACAGGAACAAUUACUAUUUCACUUGAGGAUGAAAAUGACAAUCCACCAUCUUUCACAGAAACUUCUUAUGUUACAGAAGUAGAAGAAAACAGAAUUGACGUGGAGAUUUUACGAAUGAAGGUACAGGAUCAGGAUUUGCCAAACACUCCUCACUCAAAGGCUGUAUACAAAAUCCUACAAGGAAAUGAAAAUGGAAACUUCAUAAUUAGCACAGAUCCAAAUACAAAUGAAGGAGUGCUGUGUGUUGUCAAGCCAUUGAACUAUGAAGUCAAUCGCCAAGUUAUUUUGCAAGUUGGUGUCAUUAACGAGGCACAAUUCUCUAAAGCAGCGAGCUCACAAACUCCUACAAUGUGCACUACAACUGUCACCGUUAAAAUUAUAGACAGUGAUGAGGGCCCUGAAUGCCACCCUCCAGUGAAAGUUAUUCAGAGUCAAGAUGGCUUCCCAGCUGGCCAAGAACUCCUUGGAUACAAAGCACUGGACCCGGAAAUAUCCAGUGGUGAAGGCUUAAGGUAUCAGAAGUUAGGGGAUGAAGAUAACUGGUUUGAAAUUAAUCAACACACUGGCGACUUGAGAACUCUAAAAGUACUAGAUAGAGAAUCCAAAUUUGUAAAAAACAACCAAUACAAUAUUUCAGUUGUUGCAGUGGAUGCAGUUGGCCGAUCUUGCACUGGAACAUUAGUAGUUCAUUUGGAUGAUUACAACGAUCACGCACCUCAAAUUGACAAAGAAGUGACCAUUUGUCAGAAUAAUGAGGAUUUUGCUGUUCUGAAACCUGUAGAUCCAGAUGGACCUGAAAAUGGACCACCUUUUCAAUUCUUUCUGGAUAAUUCUGCCAGUAAAAACUGGAACAUAGAAGAAAAGGAUGGUAAAACUGCCAUUCUUCGUCAACGGCAAAAUCUUGAUUAUAACUAUUAUUCUGUGCCUAUUCAAAUAAAAGACAGGCAUGGUUUAGUUGCAACACAUAUGUUAACAGUGAGAGUAUGUGACUGUUCAACUCCAUCUGAGUGUAGAAUGAAGGAUAAAAGUACAAGAGACGUUAGACCAAAUGUAAUACUUGGAAGAUGGGCUAUUCUUGCUAUGGUGUUGGGUUCUGUAUUGUUAUUAUGUAUUCUGUUUACAUGUUUCUGUGUCACUGCUAAGAGAACAGUCAAGAAAUGUUUUCCAGAAGACAUAGCCCAGCAAAAUUUAAUUGUAUCAAAUACUGAAGGACCUGGAGAAGAAGUAACGGAAGCAAAUAUUAGACUCCCCAUGCAGACAUCCAACAUUUGUGACACAAGCAUGUCUGUUGGUACUGUUGGUGGCCAGGGAAUCAAAACACAGCAAAGUUUUGAGAUGGUCAAAGGAGGCUACACUUUGGAUUCCAACAAAGGAGGUGGACAUCAGACCUUGGAGUCCGUCAAGGGAGUGGGGCAGGGAGAUACUGGCAGAUAUGCGUACACGGACUGGCAGAGUUUCACCCAACCUCGGCUUGGCGAAGAAUCCAUUAGAGGACACACUCUGAUUAAAAAUUAAACAGUAAAAGAAGGUGUAUUUGUGUGGACAAGAUGAGGAGCAUAAACAUUGUGAAGACUACGUUUGUUCGUAUAACUAUGAAGGCAAAGGUUCUCUGGCCGGCUCAGUAGGUUGCUGCAGCGAUCGGCAGGAAGAAGAGGGACUGGAGUUUCUAGAUCACCUGGAACCCAAAUUUAGGACAUUAGCAAAGACAUGCAUCAAGAAAUAAAUGUGCCUUUUAAUAGUGUAAUAUCCACAGAUGCAUAAGUAGGAAUUUAUUACUUGCAGAAUGUUAGCAGCAUCUGCUAAUGUUUUUGUUUAUGGAGGUAAACUUUGUCAUGUAUAGGUAAGGGUACUAUAAAUAUGAGAUUCCCCUACAUUCUCCUUGUCUGGUAUAACUUCCAUGUUCUCUAGAAAUCAAGGUUUUGUUUGUUAAUUCUCUUUUAUAUGCAUGUAUAUAUUGCCCUUUUCACGACUGUACUGUACACCUUCUUGCACCUUUUAUUUGCAAACUGAUGUUACUUUUUGUGCUGUGGAAGAGCAUUUGGGAAAGCUGGGUAUUAUAGAGGCCAAUGAAAGAUGAAUUUGCAUUGUAGAUGUACGAAUUAAAUAUGUUCUUCAAAAUCUUGGGGAGAAUUAUGUUCUUAGAACAUAGUUGGUGCCAGAUAAUUGCAUUCUCUCCACCUGAGUGGUUUAAAAAGGACUUUUAAGUAUUCUUCAGUGCAAUCUUCAGUUUUGUGAUUAAGUUCAUUUCUCUUUUACACUUUUGUACUCCUCAGAGCAGUGCUCCCAGCAUUGUUUUCUUUCAGGAUCCUUCAGAGCUCAGUCCCUGGACCUCUGCCCAUGUGGAUUUGUUGUUAGGUCACUCCAACUUCUAGGGUUCUUGGAAAGAUAAGGACCAGAACAAGCUCAUAGCAAAUUGAGGGGCAGAGAUUUUAUGAAGAUUACAUGAGAAGAUUUCCAUGAAAGAAUUGCAGCCCUGAGGUCCAUGGGUUGACUUAUGCUCACAAAUAUGUUUCGUUUGCUCAACAUGGUUUACUACUAACAUUUUAAAAAUAUAAAUACUUUAGCAAAAACAUUCACUCUUGAGUUUGACAUAGGCCUGCCUUAUCUGUGGUUGCCACCUGCCAUCUCCAAGCAUUUGGACAACUAGCCCUGAUGCAUUAGGCUGCAACUCUGAUAUACAGAGACUAGCACCUUGAAUAUGCCAGAAAUUGAAUUACCAUCUGUAUUAGAACUUAAGACUCAGCCUAAAUUUACAGUUACUUUAAGAAAAUGGGCAGUCAGAAUUAGGGACUAGAAUGUAUAUGAGAAACCCCCACUCUACUAAAAAUAUAAGAAAUUAGCCGGACAUGGUGGCGAAUGACUGUAAUCCCAGCUACUCAGGAGGCUGAGGCAGGAGAAUCGCUUGAAUCCAGGAGGCGGAGGUUGCAGUGAGCCGAGAUUGCCACUGCACUCCAGCCUGGGCAACAAGAGCGAAACUCCGUCUCAAAAAAAAAAAAAAAAA